GCCUCGGCGCGUGUAUUGGCUCCUUCGGCUGCGGGCCGGCUCGGCUACGCGCUCUGCUCCGAGCCGCUCACUGCAUGGUAGAGUCUGGUGCCCCCGCCGCCGCCUGCAUCGCCGCCACCGCCGCUCCGCCACGACCACCGCCGCCUCCUGCCCUGCAGCCACCGCCACCGCCUGUGUCGCCGCCGCCUCGGGACCGGCUGUAUGAUUAGGCCACAAUCUUCAAUGAGUAAACAUAUUCCUCAAUUCUGUGGUGUUCUUGGUCACACAUUUAUGGAGUUUCUGAAGGGCAGUGGAGAUUACUGCCAGGCACAGCACGACCUCUAUGCAGACAAGUGAACUGUAGAAACUGAUUACUGCUCCACCAAGAAGCCCCCAUAAGAGUGGUUAUCCUGGACACAGAAGUGUUGAAUUGAAAUCCACAGAGCAUUUUACAAGAGUUCUGACCUGGAUGGGGUAAACCUCAGUGCACUUCUUUUCUGUUGGCCUCAGUAUUACUGGAUUGAAGAAUUGCUGCUUCUUGUUAGGAGGUUCAUUUCACUUAUCAUUACUUACAACUUCAUACUCAAAGCACUGAGAAUUUCAAGUGGAGUAUAUUGAAGUAGACUUCAGUUUCUUUGCAUCAUUUCUGUAUUCAAUUUUUUUAAUUAUUUCAUAACCCUAUUGAGUGUUUUUUAACUAAAUUAACAUGGCUCGAAUGAACCGCCCAGCUCCUGUGGAAGUCACAUACAAGAACAUGAGAUUUCUUAUUACACACAAUCCAACCAAUGCGACCUUAAACAAAUUUAUAGAGGUAAGAUUUGAUAUGUUUUAGUAGCUUAAAUUGAUUGCAAUAUAAUAGUGGGACUUAUAGCUAACAAAAUAAAAACUACUUUGGAAAAAAUGAGAUGAUAUACCUACAAUUCCAGUUCCCAGAAAUAAAUGUCAAUGUCUUCUAUAGGUUAGAGGUAUAUUUGUACAUUUUGAGAAGGGCAUGUGCUUGAGUUAAUAGUUAUUGUACCUGAGUUUGCUUGAAUUGGUAUGUGGACAGUAAAACAGUAUAGCUCUUACUUAUCUUGUAAGAAAUUUACAUGGGAAAGGUUGCCAUUUAUGGAUUUUUUAUAUAUCUGCUUAACCUAAUGACUAAUGCCAUAAACCAGUUGGUUUUUCUUGAACCCCAUCUGAUGCUUAGAAUCCAAUUUUCAACUACAAAUUCUGUUCCUUCCUAAUGGUAGCUAUGUAGCCAAAACUCUACCUGCCUCUUUUUACUAGGAGAAAGGAAUUGAAUGCUGAAUAAUAUAUCGGGAUGUGCACAUGUUUUAUUUUAUAAAUACCUACAGUUGUUAAGAAAUAGCAAAUAGGCCUCUCAGAACAUAAUGGAAAUACUUUUUUUUCCUUUUUUUGAGAUGGAGUCUCGUUCUGUCACCCAGGCUGGAGUGCAGUGGCAUGAUCUCAGCCCACUGCAACCUCUGCCUCCCGGGUUCAAGCAAUUCUCCUGCCUCAGCCUCCCAAGUAGCUGAGACUACAGGCGUACGCCACCUUGCCCAGCUAAUUUUUGUAUUUUUAGAUGUAGUUUCACCAUAUUGGCCAGGCUGGUCUCGAACUCCUGACCUCAGGUGAGCCACCACGCCUGGCUGGGAAAUACUUUAAUGGUACUUUAAUUUUUAUUACUAUAUAUUAUAUAUACACUAAUAUAUACUAUAUAGUGUAUAUAAUAGUAUAUUAUAUUAGUAAUAUGUAAUUAGUAAUAAUGCAUUUUGAAGCCUGUAGUUUUAAAUGGUAUGUGGGCUUUUUUACUGUAGUUAAGACUUCAUUCAAUGUAAAUCAGUAAAGUUUAAGGAGUGAGUAUAAUUGAGUGAAGUCAGAUUACCCGAUUAGUUAUAAAUAAUGCCUUUAGUUACAUUUACCUUUGUCUGCAUUGCUGCUAGCCCCUUUUGGUUAAUGUUUCAUCCCAAUCCGGUAUUACCAUGACUGUAAACAACUUCAGUGUAUGAAGGGGGCACACAAUUUAAACAAAAGAAGGAAAACUUUUCCAGUUUAUUAAAAAUAUGUAUGGUAUUUAAUAUUCACUUUUCUUUUUAUAUUCUAGCAUUGUCACUUAAAACAAAAUUUGCUUUUGUGUUAAACAUAAAUGGAUUCUAGCAUUCUUUAAAUGAUCUUCUGUUAACCAGCAUACUUACUGAUCAGAGAUGAUCAGAAUAUAAAAUGUUGAGUUAUAGUGAUGUGGUUAAACAUUAAGAUUUUUUUAAUGUACGUUUUAUCCAGGAACUUAAGAAGUAUGGAGUUACCACAAUAGUAAGAGUAUGUGAAGCAACUUAUGACACUACUCUUGUGGAGAAAGAAGGUAUCCAUGUUCUUGUAAGUAUUUAACAGUUCUUAUGGGUUUAUGGUGCUGUGCUACAAAAGUUUAUUCAAAUAGUAAAUUCAAAUAAAUAUCUAUUUAAGUCAUAAAUAGACCUCAAAAAGCUAAAAACAAAUAUUAUAUUAUUGUGCAGAAUCUUAAUUUCUAAAUAAAGGUGAAAAGCUAAGCAAGGAUUUGAAGUUGUGAAACAUUUUUGUAAAGAUUGAGCAUUUAGUCACAUUUGGUAGACAACAGGGUUUAAUAAGAUUUGAUUAAACAUUAAAAUGAGAAUGCUUUUGAAAACAUUUCCAUGUUAGAAAUUUAGAAUUAUUACUACAGUGUUUAUAUUAAUGAUCUAAAAUGUUUAAAUAUUCUUCUGACUUAGGAUUGGCCUUUUGAUGAUGGUGCACCACCAUCCAACCAGAUUGUUGAUGACUGGUUAAGUCUUGUGAAAAUUAAGUUUCGUGAAGAACCUGGUUGUUGUAUUGCUGUUCAUUGCGUUGCAGGCCUUGGGAGGUAAAUGAAUUUAUCAAUUUGAUUCUAGGUAAAAAUCUAUUGAUAAUGAAAAUACAGAAACUUGAAAAAUUCUUAUAAUUUUUUAAUAUAAAGUCAACAUUUGUCAUAGGUAUUACUUAAAUAGGAAGGGUGGUAGAUAAUACUUCUGAGUUGGGGAAUGUUUGGAGAAAUAAAUUUACAAAGAUCUGAUUUUGAAAAAACUAUUUAUCAAAAUUCUUACCUCACCAGAGCUCCAGUACUUGUUGCCCUAGCAUUAAUUGAAGGUGGAAUGAAAUACGAAGAUGCAGUACAAUUCAUAAGACAGUAAGUAAUGGAUUCUCUUUUCAUUUGUACUCUCUUUCAUUUCCUUGUUGAGUGUCAGUGAGUUUAAUAGUCUAAUAGCCCAUUUAAUCAUUAUGAUUAUUUUUUGAGAUAGUAUUAAAACCAGGAAAUCAAGAUCUUACAUUCUUUUUUGCAUUUCAUGCAGUUGCUCAUAUUACUAAGAUUCUAAUCCAACAAGAGUUUUUGAAUUAUUGUUUUGCUUUAAAUACUUGAUUGAAUAUGUUGGUUAUUUUGUAUUUUUAUUGAGGUAUAAUUAAGAUACAUUUAAAGAUACAAUAAAAUGCACAGGUCUCCAAAGGAGACCAGUUGACAAUAACAGCCAAAUUAACCAUCCAAUACAACACAUAGAAUAUUUUGAGUGCUGUAGAACAUGCCUUUGUGGCUUUUGUAGUCAUCUUCCCUGCUACCAGAGGCAACUUCUGACUUCACUAUAAAUUAGUUUUGUCUUUUCGUGGACUUACGUGUAAAUGGAUUUGUGAGUCGACUGUUGUAACCAAUACUCAAACGAAGAUAUAAAGAAAAUUAACUUUUUAUGAUUUUUUCCAUUUACACUGAUGUGCCUGUUCAUAUUCCUUUCUGCAUCAGGUCACAGCCUAAUUAAUCAAAAGAUAAAUUGCCACAAGAGAGGUGAUGGUUGUCUAUAAGACACUAAAUAUUACUGUAGGGGGCUUUUGCCUUGUUUCAUUUUUUUUUUUUUUUCCUCCCAGAAAGCGGCGUGGAGCUUUUAACAGCAAGCAACUUCUGUAUUUGGAGAAGUAUCGUCCUAAAAUGCGGCUGCGUUUCAAAGAUUCCAACGGUCAUAGAAACAACUGUUGCAUUCAAUAAAAUUGGGGUGCCUAAUGCUACUGGAAGUGGAACUUGAGAUAGGGCCUAAUUUGUUAUACAUAUUAGCCAACAUGUUGGCUUAGUAAGUCUAAUGAAGCUUCCAUAGGAGUAUUGAAAGGCAGUUUUACCAGGCCUCAAGCUAGACAGAUUUGGCAACCUCUGUAUUUGGGUUACAGUCAACCUAUUUGGAUACUUGGCAAAAGAUUCUUGCUGUCAGCAUAUAAAAUGUGCUUGUCAUUUGUAUCAAUUGACCUUUCCCCAAAUCAUGCAGUAUUGAGUUAUGACUUGUUAAAUCUAUUCCCAUGCCAGAAUCUUAUCAAUACAUAAGAAAUUUAGGAAGAUUAGGUGCCAAAAUACCCAGCACAAUACUUGUAUAUUUUUAGUACCAUACAGAAGUAAAAUCCCAGGAACUAUGAACACUAGACCUUAUGUGGUUUAUUCCUUCAAUCAUUUCAAACAUUGAAAGUAGGGCCUACAUGGUUAUUUGCCUGCUCACUUUAUGUUUACAUCUCCCACAUUCAUACCAAUAUACGUCAGGUUUGCUUAACCAUUGAUUUUUUUUUUUUUUUACCAAGUCUUACAGUGAUUAUUUUACGUGUUUCCAUGUAUCUCACUUUGUGCUGUAUUAAAAAAACCUCCAUUUUGAAAAUCUACGUUGUACAGAAGCACAUGUCUUUAAUGUCUUCAGACAAAAAAGCCUUACAUUAAUUUAAUGUUUGCACUCUGAGGUGCAACUUAACAGGGAGGGCCUGAGAAAAGAAUGGGAGGGGGCUAUUAAUUAUUUUUAGCAAAAUGUUGCCUUUGUCUUGUGCAAACAUGUAGAAUAUGCUCUUUAAUUUAGUAAAAUAUUUUUUUAAAAGGUAGAGAUGCUUUGUUAUUGUAAUCAUAAACUUCCUGAAAUUCUUGUAAUUUUUUUCCCAUACUUAUCAGAAGUGUGUUUACCAACUUAUUUUUGUUUGAAAGUGUGAUUUUUUUUUUCCUUCCCAACCUCUCUUGCAAAAAAAGAAAUGGGUUUCUGCUAAUGAAUUGAGCAGACAUCUAAUAUUUUAUAUGCCUUUUGAGCUGUGUAACUUAAUAUUUGGAUACUUGACAAUUUGUUUUAUUAUGUAAUUGAUAAAAUGGUGAUGUGUAUUAAUGUUAGUUCAACCAUAUAUUUAUACUGUCUGGGGAUGUGUGGUUAUAGUUCUGUGGGAGAAAUAAUUUUGUCAGUGUUCACCAGCUUGUAAAAACUUAGUGCGAGAGCUGAAACAUCUAAAUAAAUAAUGACAUGCAUUUAUCAUCAUUGAGAUUGGUUUGCUUAAAAUUAACUUAUUUUGUAGAAGACAAAAUGAAUUGCACUUCACUUAAUGUGUGUCCUCAUCUUUUUACAAAUAAAUGAAGGAUUAUAAAUGAUGUCAGCAUUUUAGUAAACUUUUAGACAAAAUUUGUUAGGGUCAUUCAUGAAAACUUUAAUACUAAAAGCACUUUCCAUUAUAUACUUUUUAAAGGUCUAGAUAAUUUUGAACCAAUUUAUUAUUGUGUACUGAGGAGAAAUAAUGUAUAGUAGAGGACAGCCUUGGUUUGUAAAGCUCAGUUCCACUAGUUCAUGGUUUUGUGCAACUUCUGAGCCUCAGUUUUCUCCUUUGCAAAUUAAUAAUUACAUACCUUUAUAGAUUUUGAAAUUAAUUUAAAUAUUAGUAUUUGGUACAUGAAGGCUUAAUGUUAAGUUUCCUUUAAUGAUCCACAAUAAUCCCUUUGAUCACGUUAAUCUAAAUCUAGAUGUCUUUGUCUAAUUUUUUUUGAAUAGCAGUUAUAAAUGUAAAGGACUCAAAGUUUAAGUAAAAAGUGAUACUCCACCUUGUGUUUCAAAGAAUUUAGUUCCACCUCUUCAUACCAGUUUAACACUUAAUAUAUUUCAUUGGAUUUUAGACAGGGCAAAAGGAAGAACAGGGGCCUCUGGAGGCCCUUGGUUAUUUAAAUCUUGGAUUAUUUGUGAUAGUAAUCACAAAUUUUUGGCUAAUUUUUAACCUGAGGUUUUGUUUUUUUUUUAAAGGAAAUGCAGCCUAGUCUUGAGAACAUAAUUUUAUAUAAUCAAUUACUAAAUGUUAAACUAUUACCACACAGCCCAUAAAACAGCAUUUGCGUUUAUUGAGAGAGAGGAUGUGCCAUCAUGAUUAAUGAAAACUAUCUUUUGAGUUUGAAAAGAAAUUAAUUUGCAGUGUUUGGAUUGUAUAUAUGGUGCUAAAAAUAAAUUAAUUUACUUUAUAAACCUUAUCUGUACAUUAUACGAUGUGAUGAAAUUUGCUUUUUAUCCAAAUAUUUUGUAUCUUGUAAAUAUGGCUAAUUAUAGGAAUGCCUAUAAUACAUCUUAGAUUCCUUAUAUCUAAUAAGAGUUCAAAGAGUUAUGAGUUGAAGUCUUGAAUGCAGGAAACUAUCUGAUAGUGUUCUAAAAUUUGGUUACUUGGGUUUGGAUACCCUUAGUGGGAUGAUGUAAAUAGAGGCUAGCUACCUAGGCUUGUCUAUAGCAACCAUAAUGUUGAUGUAAGUAAUGCGGUUACUGAAUCAUAAGAAAAUGCCAUCUCUUUUUAGUUGAAGGAAAACUCUGGAAGUAGGUGCCAUUGGUCAUUCUGCAGUGCACUGCAACCAUUGUUUCCCCUAGUGCCCUCUUUUCCCUAGGGCAUUGCUCUCCUAUUCCCACGCCUUAACACAGCUCUAUACCUAGAAGCAGCCAGCCCAGGCAUGCAGUCACAUUUAAUCACAUCCCCCUUCUAGAGUGCUUCAAAAUGAUGUAGUCCCUCAACUUGGCUAAAGAAUCUCAAUCUCUUGAAAUUUAUUUUUUUAAUGUCAUAUUCAUCUGGUAAAUAUCUACUGUUUGCCAGGCAUUUAAGAAUAUGGCAAAGAACAUAAAAGAUGGUGUCACCAGAUUUUGGUCACCAAUGAGUACCCGACCCGUUGCCAUGAUUAAGAGAGAAUGCUUUCUAUUGGAGUUUCAGGAAAUAUAAUUUGAGAAUACUUUAAAGGGAAGUGGAAGUAUAAGUGAAUGAUAUUUUUCUUUUACAUGUAAACAAUGAAGUUAUUUCAAAGUUAAGUUUUAAACAAAAUACAUGAAGUAGUGUCUGCCAUACAUGUUAAUAUUCUACAUUCUUGCUUCCUUAAAUUAAUAUGUUUGUGUGUAUAUAUGUGCCUCACACCUGAAUUGAAAAUUAAAGACUGGUUUAAAAGUGGUUUAAAAGUGACAUUUAAUGUUUCUCCAUUACGUUUGGGGUAACCAGCCUAAGUGGAAUCUUGGAAGGAAAGUAAGGGAAAAACUUGUAUUUGCCUUCAAUGAAUUAAACCAGUGAUAUGUGUUAACGUAUGAAUGAAAGGAUUGAUGGUGAUUUUAUAAUUAUAUAUAUUGCCGCAGUAACCAGUUAAUAAAUUGAUAGCUACCAUUUA